ACACACUCACAAACUCACUCACUGACACACUCACACACUCACUUACACCUCCCCCAGCUCACCUCCUCCCCACCCCAGCAUGGCCGCGUCCACCAUGUCCAUCCGCUCCAGCGCUUACUCCGACUCCUGGCAGGUGGACGACUGCCCAGAGAGCUGCUGUGAGCCCCCCUGCUGCGCCACCAGCUGCUGCGCCCCGGCCCCCUGCCUGACCCUGGUCUGCACCCCAGUGAGCCGUGUAUCCAGCCCCUGCUGCCAGGUGACCUGUGAGCCCAGCCCCUGCCAAUCAGGCUGCACCAGCUCCUGCACGCCCUCGUGCUGCCAGCAGUCUAGCUGCCAGCCGGCUUACUGCACCUCCUCCCCCUGCCAGCAGGCCUGCUGCGUGCCCGUCUGCUGCAAGCCUGUGUGCUGCGUGCCCGUCUGCUGUGGGGCUUCUUCGUGCUGCCAACAGUCUAGCUACCAGCCAGCUUGCUGUGCCUCUUCCUCCUGCCAGCCGGCCUGCUGUGUGCCCGUCUGCUGCAAACCUGUGUGCUGUGCGCCCACCUGCUCUGAGGAUUCCUAUUCAUGCUGCCAACAGUCUAGCUGCCAGCCAGCUUGCUGCACUUCCUCCCCCUGCCAGCAGUCCUACUGUGUGCCUGUCUGCUGUAAGCCUGUCUGCUGCAAACCCAUCUGCUGUGUGCCUGUCUGCUCUGGGGCUUCCUCUUUGUGCUGCCAGCAGUCUGGCUGCCAGCCGGCUUGCUGCACCACCUCCUGCUGCAGACCCUCCUCCUCUGUGUCCCUCCUCUGCCGCCCUGUGUGCAGGCCCGCCUGCUGCGUGCCCGUCUCCUCCUGCUGUGCCCCCACCUCCUCCCGCCAGCCCAGCUAUUGCCGCCAGGCCUCCUGUGUGUCCCUUCUCUGCCGCCCUGUGUGCUCCCGCCCGGCCUGCUACAGCUUCUCCUCAGGCCAGAAGUCCAGCUGCUGACGGUCAUGUCCCCCAGGGCCAGCCGGGCUCAGGCCCCACCUCCCUGCCAGUCCUUGGACCUCCCAGCCCACCCAGCCUCAGCACAGCUCAACACAGAAGGAGCAGCCCCAGCCACAGCCGCCCAGCCCCGGGGUCUCAGAUGCUCACUGGCUCCUCCCUGACCUCCCCCCCGGGCAGGCGAGCCCUGGCUUCUCCUCACGGUGCUUCCUGGCUGCAGACCACAACCCUCCGCUGGUCGCUGGUUGGGGACGGGCCCUCCUGACCCGGGUCUCACCCCCAGCAGCGUCACCCUCUGCCCCUGAGCACCAAUAAAGCGUCUGCGGCCCCA